GUUUGUUUGGACUGGAGAAGGGAGGCGGCGGGCGAAGCGCACGUCGAGCGGGGGAGCGGCGCUGCCUGUGGAGAUCCGCGGAGGCCGACAGGAUUCGUUGGCUGCCGUCCCCGCUGCUGUGCAUUGGGUGAGGGGUCCUCUCGGGCAGAGUGGCGACAGGGGUGCGGAGGUCGAGGGACAGCAAGUCGGCGACGGCAGAGGGGCCUAAAGGGUUCCCUGGGUGGUUGGCCACCGAGUCCAUUGCGGCCUCCGUUGUUCAUUGCCUCUUUCCACCAAGUCUGAGGGAUGAGCUUGGGCCGACUUCGUCUCUGUCUUCUCCGAGACAUGGCCGUCGCUUUUUUUUCAUUGUCAUUAUUAAUGAUUUGGAUCUCGCAGCUCUCUAUCCGGGUCCUCAGUGGCGCGAGGGUUGCCGGGAUAGCACUUUCUCCUGUUCCUCAUUCUCCCGGUCCUUUAUCCCUCCGCCGGGUACCCUUUCCCCUGCCCCCCUCCCACCGCCUCGGCAACAAAGCUUAUUGUUUCUACCCACUUUACGCCUGCGCGUCGCCACGCGCAGCCCCUACUUGCUGCGCGUGCGCGCCUCAGCCGAGGCUGGGGUUUGGGGAGAGAGGGGCGGAGGGACUGGCGGGCUCUUGGCGUCUUGGGGGAACGCUGCAACCGUCGACGGGCCUGAUCAGAAGAUCGUCUUUCUCCCGUUUCUUCGCCAUCGCUACCCCUUAUUUUUGGUUGUAUUGCAGCUCAUGCCCUGGAAAAAAGAACCUUUGGGGUACUGGGAACCCUUACCCUAGGAGGGCGUUGAGUUAGAUGAACUUUAAGGUCCUCUUACCUUUUAAUAAUUUUCUGUGCUUACUCUCCUCCUUCCCCACCAUCGCCACCAGAAAUAAAUAAGGCUUGUGGUGAACUUAGGUCUUCAAAACAUUUGUUGCAGCAGCCAGCAGUGAUAUUUUUUAGGGACUCCUAAAAGGGGUCUUACCUGCUUCCUUUUGUUUCUUUUUUCCCUGAUUUGGCACCCGUAUCAACUCAUAAAAACCCCAAACUCUAGAAAGAAUUUGGCUUCCAAUUUGCCUUGGAAGGUGUAGCAGCUGACAGCCUUUGACGUUUAUUUCAACGGAAAGUAGAUGUUCAUGUUGGGUGUGCUGGCUAAUGUUGAAACGUGGUGGCAUUGUUUUUUCACAGAUUUCAUUAGCACAGUUAGAUCAGGUGUUGGUUUAUAUUUUCAUUAAGUCGCUUUUGAAAUUUCUUCUGGCGUAGGUUGUGUUUGCAAUAAGUAAAAGUUCUCUACAAUAAUUUUUAAUGAGACUCCACUAUUUGCUUUUGUGAUUCUGUUUCCAGUUAGUGAAAGACAGGAUAUUUGGGGAAAAUUAGUCUGUUUAUACUACUUGUCAGUUGUGAACUUGAAUAAAACUUUUUCACACACACACAAAAUCACAGGAUAGGUAACUUGACAAGAACUAUAGAACCCACUUGUGUUUCUUUAAGGGAUGGAGGUUAGGGAAUGGAGAUUUCCUCUAAUGAUUCAAGGCUGUGCACGUUGCUCCUUAGGAACUCAAAUUGAGGUUAAAAACGACAACCAACAUCAGCCAUGAAAGAUCCAAGUCGCAGCAGUACUAGCCCAAGCAUCAUCAAUGAAGAUGUGAUUAUUAACGGUCAUUCUCAUGAAGAUGACAAUCCAUUUGCAGAGUACAUGUGGAUGGAAAAUGAAGAAGAAUUCAACAGACAAAUAGAAGAGGAGUUAUGGGAAGAAGAAUUUAUUGAACGCUGUUUCCAAGAAAUGCUGGAAGAGGAAGAAGAGCAUGAAUGGUUUAUUCCAGCUCGAGAUCUCCCACAAACUAUGGACCAAAUCCAAGACCAGUUUAAUGACCUUGUUAUCAGUGAUGGCUCUUCUCUGGAAGAUCUUGUGGUCAAGAGCAAUCUGAAUCCAAAUGCAAAGGAGUUUGUUCCUGGGGUGAAGUACGGAAAUAUUUGAGUAGACGGGGCCCUCUUUUGGUGGAUGUAGCACAAUUUCCACACUGUGAAGGCAGUAUUAGAAGACUUAAUUGUAAAAGCUCUCUUGUCACUGUGUUACACUUAUGCAUUGCCAAAGUUUUUGUUAGUCUUGCAUGCUUAAUAAAAGUGCUGAGACUGUUACUAAGUAAAAAGCUGUCAAACAUUUACUGAAAAUAGAAUUGGCCCCAUGGCUUGAUGUGAAGACAGCAAGGAAAGAAGCACCAGUCAAGUUGUGAACAAGCACCAAAUUAAAAGACCUAAACCUUACCAAAUUGUCUUUUUUUGAGGCUAAUCUAUCACUUGUUAAUGUCUAAACUUUAAAAUCAGUACAUUUAAUUUGAGUUCCAACUGUUAAGCAUAUUUCUCAGACUUAAAUUUGAUUAUGUCCCCAUCAAAAAGAAUCUCCAUUUUCUGAAGGUCUGUUAGUUAAUUUGAGAUAAUUUGUUAAAGGCAAGUAUGUCAUAUUACUGAGGCUACAAGUUAGUCAGCAGAUGAGUGCCAGUCCAGCCUUUUCUGGUAUGUUAUUGUUAGAAAUAUUGAGUUCUAAUGUUACAUCUGAGGAAGUAUGUAAUUUGAGAAUUGUAACUUCUAAGGGAUUCACUGCAUCAUAGCUAUGCCUGUAUGGAGUCUAACAUAUGACCAAUACCAACCCAUAAUCCAGCUGAACAAAGAUACUGUAACAUGAUUUGAGUGGUGCUUUUCCUUGCUUUGUUAACCAUCACGAGAGUCUGCAGCACAACUUUUAACAAAGCUAGAACAGUUUUGGCUUCUUAAACUUCAUAUUUGGGUAGGUUAAGCUGCCAUACGUGUUCAGUGUGAAUAGUGUUUAAGUUGAAAAUAUUGUAAAAAAAUUAUAUUUUUUCAAAAAUAUUUAAAAAAAUAAAUAAUAGUAGAACUGA